GGCACGGUGGCUCACGCCUGUAAUCCCACCACUUUGGGAGGCCGAGGUGGGCAGAUCAUGCCGUCAGGACUUCAAGACCAGCCUGGCCAGCGUGGUGAAACCCCGUCUCUACUAAAAAUACAAAAAUUAGCCAGGCAUGGUGGUGGGCACCUGUAAUCCCAGCUACUCGGGAGGCUGAGGCGGGAGAAUCCCUUGAACCCGGGAGGCGGAGGUUGCAGUGAGCUGAGAUCGUGUCACUGCACUCCAGCCUAGGUGACAGAGCGAGACUCCGUCUCAAAAAACAAAAACAGAAAACAGCAGUUCAUAAAGAUAUAUAGUCAAGGAUUUUUUUUUUUUUUUCCAGGAGUCUUGCUCUGUCGUCCAGGCUGGAGUGCAGUGACACCAUCUUGGCUCACUGCCAUCUCUGUCUCCUGGGUUCAAGUGAUUCUCCUGCCUCAACCUCUGGAGUAGCUAGGAGUAUAGGAGCCCACCAUCAUGCUGGCUAAUUUUUUUGUAUUUUUAGUAGAGAGAGCGUUUCACUAUGUUGGCCAGUCUGGUCUCAAACUCCUGACCUCAAGUGAUCCGAUGCCUCCGCCUCCCAAAGUGCUGGGAUUACAGGCAUGAGCCACCACACCCAGCCAUGGUCAAGGAUGUUUACUGGAAACAUUGUUAGUAAGGAUAAGAUAGUAGAAACAAAGUGAUUGCUCGUAAUAGUUGAAUCAGUUUUGGUAUAUUCAUAGGAUGAAAUACAUUGCAUCUUCCUUGGAAGAAUUUCCAUGAAAUGGUAUUGACUGAAAAAGAAUAUGACAGCAUCCCAUUUUUUAGUUAAAAAAUUAUUUAAUAACAUCCCAUUUUUAAAAAAUAUUAAAAAACAUCCCAUAUAUAUAUAUGGGUUAUAUAUAAAACCCAUAUUAUAUAUAUAUAAAAAUGUGUGUGUUUAUGAUUAUGACUAUGGGAGGAACAAGAAAGGAUGCCUGAUGUUAACAUGUUAUCUGGGAGUGAGAAUUAACAUAGGAGGAAAGAGAGAAGGGAGAUGAAAAGGAGAUUAAAAAAAAAAAAGGAGAUAAAGCGUUCCCACCUCAGCAUGAAUGCUGUCUCAAUUAUUUUAAAUAGUAUUUUGUGUAACUGUGGCUGUAUGUGUACACAUGAAAAAGAAGAGUUAUAUGCAUAGCUAAUAGAUACAGUCUUUAUGUCCAUGAUAUGUGAUAAAAAGCAGGUUGAUGUAUAUUGUAUGUAUCUAUUUCAGUAAAAAUAAAACAAAGACCACAAAAAUCCUUGUAUAUGUGGAGAAAGGUAUGGAAGGAAACACAUCAGGCCACUAUUUGAGUACUUCAAUGAGUAGGAUUGGGGUGAGCUUUUUCUCAAACAUUGUAUUUUUUUUUUCGCUUGGUAUAAGAAGUGAGCAUUGUUUGUAAUUUGAAAAACAGCAAAGAAAAAAUGUAAUUGUGUUCUACUCAUUUAAUAAUGGCCAUGUGGGUGAAACUUGUGCAAAUGAAAAGGUUAAUAUGUGCAAUGAAAAGGUUAAUAAUAGGCAAAAAGACUCCAGAAAUGAUUUAUGUGCAAAUGAAAGGUUAAUAAUGGGCAAAAGACUCCAAAAACGAUCAACAAAUGGGAGUGGGAUCAGAUUUUAUUACUUUUGGCCAAAGGCCAUUUCAAAAUAUUAGUAAGACUGUUAUUCAGAAAUACUGAAGGGGAGACAUGGUAAAGUUUCUUCCACUGUAAAGUGAAACAACGGAAAGUAAGGAACCUUGAGGAACAAUUUUAAAUUGUAGAGUAAUAGCUUAGUGUUCAACAGAUAAGAUUUGCCUUUCCUGAUAACUCUGCCAACAGAGUUAUUUUGUUAGCGGCAGAAUAUCACAGUGGUUCAGAGCAAGAGCUUUGUUUAGAAGUACCUACUACUAGCUGUGUGCCUUCAUUUUUCUCAUAGGAAAGUUAGAGAAUGGCCGGGUGCAGUGGCCCAUACCUGUAAUCCCAGCACUUUGGGGGGCUGAGGUGGGCGGAUCACCAGGUCAGGAGAUCGAGACCAUCCUGGCUAACACGGUGAAACCCCAUCUCUACUAAAAAUACAAAAAAUUAGCUGGGUGUAGUGGCGGGCACCUGUGGUCCCAGCUACUCGGGAGGCUGAGGCAGGAGAAUGGCACGAACCCAGGAGGCAGAGGUUGCAGUGAGCUGAGAUCGCGUCACUGCACUCCAGCCUGGGUGACAGAGCGAGACUUCCUCUCAAAAAAAAAAAAAAAAAAAUACAAAAAGAAAGUUAGAGAAUAACAGUAACUACUUCAUAAAUGUAUUGUAAGGAUUAAAUGAGUUAAUCUUUAAGGUGCUAAGAAGUAAUCUAAUACAAAAAUAAUUCCUGAGUUAAGUGUUAUUAGCUAUAUGGAUCUAAAAUGCUGGUUUUGAAUAGAACACUUCUAAUGAAGUAUUCAUUGUGUAAAAGAAUCCUAACAAUUCACCUUACACAGUAAGAGCCGUGCCCAGCACAGUGUUUUGCUUUAGUACAUGCUUUACAAAUACUGGUGGAAUAAAUAAUUUUCAUUCCUUUCACAUAAUUUUAUUAGAGUGUCUGAUUAGUUCAACAUUAUUUCACAUAUUUUGAUUAAUAUAGGAUUUCAGAAAUUAAUGCCAGUCAAAUUAAUGUUUGACUUCAGAAAAUUAGGAGGAAAAGAACAUUUAUAGGGUGAUAACUAUUACCUAUAAUAAUUUUUUUUUCUUUGGAGACAGAGUUUUGCUCUUCUUGUCCAGGCUGGAGUACAGUGGCACGAUGUUGGCUCACUGCAACCUACUCCUCCCAGGUUCAAGGGAUUCUCCUGCCUCAGUCUCCCGAGUAGCUGGGACUAGGUGAUAAUAGUUAUCACCCUAGUUGGAAUUGGAUUCAAGAAUGAAAGCGACUCCUGUGUACAUAAAUAUACACAGCUUUCAAUGGGGGGAAUGUGAGUAUGCUAACUUGUGCUUUCAACAGUCAUUACACAUUAUCACAACUUUAUAUAGAAAAGGAAUCUAAACAAUUUUGUUUAUUGUACUACCAUUUGAUUUUUAAAUUCUCUUUCACUGUUGUUUUCAUUCCUUCGUUUUUGUUUAAAUUUUUAUUUUGUUCUUUUCUUUUCUAGAGACAGGGUCUUGCUCUUUUGUUCAGGCUGGAGUGCAGUGGCACGAUUAUAGCCCACUGCAGCCUCAACGUCCCAGGCUCAAGCGAUACUUCCACCCCAGCCUCAGCCUCCAGAGUAGCUGGGAAUGCCAGCAUGCACUAUGACACUCUGCUAAUUUUUUUAUUUUUUGUACAUACGGGGUCCCACUAUCUUAUUGAGGUUAGUCUGAAACUCCUGGGCUCAAGUGAUCCUCCUGCCUGGCCUCUCAAGGUGCUGGGAUUAUAGGCAUGAGCCACCGUGCCUAGCCCAUUCCUUCAUUUAGUACACACUUUAUGUAUUUAGUAGUAUACUUUUAUUAUGUAUUUCUUUAGUAUACACUUUUAUUUACUAUUUAUUUAUGAUUUACAGGGCCUUGCUGUCUCCCAGGCUGGAGUGCAGUGGUGUGAUCAUAGCUCACUGCAUUCUUGACCUCCUGAGCUCAAUUGAUCCUCUUGCCUCAGCCUCCUGAGUAGCUGGGAGUACAGGUGUGCGCCACCACACCUGGCUAAUUUUUGUAUUUUUUGUAGAGAUGGGGUCUCCCUAUGUUGCCCAGGUUGGUCGUGAACUCCUGUGCUCAAGUGAUCCUCCUGCUUCAGUCUCCCAAAGUGCUAGGAUUACAGGCAUGAGCCGCCACACCCUGCCACUAUACACUUUUAUUUGUGUUGAUUUUGUUAAUUUAUAUUGGGCUAGAUAAUCAUCCAUUUCAUCUAGGUUUCCAAAUAUAUGGUGCUAGAGUAUAUCACUAUGCAUGAAUGUCCUCUUCUAAUUUAAAAAAUACUUGAAAAAAAAGUUGUCUUUUUUUAUUUUUAUUUUUUAUUUAUUUAUUUUUUUGAAUCUUGCUCUGUCACCAGGCUGGAGUGCAGUGGUGUGAUCUCGGCUCACCGCAACCUCUGCCUCCUGGGUUCAAGCGAUUCUCCUGCCGCAGCCUCCCGAGUAGCUGGGACUACAGGAGUGCACCAGCACGCCUGGCUAAUUUUUGUAUUUUUAUUAGAGAUGGGGUUUCACCAUCUUGACCUUGUGAUCCACCUGCCUCGGCCUUUCAAAGUGCUGGGAUUAGAAGUGUGAGCCAUCGCGCCUGGCCAACAGUUUUGUCUUUUAUAUAUGGUUCUUUUUUCUUGUCCCCAGAUAUUUUUUUUAAUCUUUUCCUAUCUUAAUCUGGCAUUAUCUAUUUCAUUGUUUUUCCAAAGAAAUUGCUUUUGUAAAUAUUUAUUCUUUAUAACACAUUUUGUUUUCUAGUCUGUUAAUUUCAGUUUUUACUCUUUUAUUUCAGUUUUUCACUCUUCCUAAUUUUGUUGAAUUUUUAAAAAUUUAAAUUUACAUAUGGUAAAGUUUACUUUUUUGGUGUACAUUUCCAUGAAUAUUUACACAUGCAUAGAUUCUUGUAAUCACCACAGACAGGACACAGAAUGAUUUGAACAACUCCAGGAAUUCCCAAGUGCUGCCCCUUUGUAUUCACACUAUCCUGCCACCCUAACCCCUGGCAACCACUGAUAUGCUUUUUGUUCCUUUAGUUUUGCUUUUUCCAGAAUCUCAUACAUAGACUUAAUGUAGUAUGUAACCUUUUAAGACGGGAUUUUCAGCCUGGGCAACAAAGUGAGACAUCUCUACAAAAAAUUAAAAAAAAAUUAGCCGGGCAUGGUGGCACACAUCUGUAGUCCCAGCUACUUGAGUAGCUGAGGUGGAAGGGGAGGGGUUUUAGGUUGCAGUGAGCCAAGAUCGUGCCACUGCACUCCAGCCUGGGUGACAGCGCAAGACUGUCUCAAAAAAAAAAAAAAAAUUCUCGUAAGGAACAUGCAGCCUAGAACCCUCGCAGGCACCUGUGCAGUUUAAUAGGGUUCACACUCUUGUGAAAAUGUAAUGCCUCUGCUGAUCUGACAGGAGGCAGAGCUCAGGCAAUGAAGUGAGCAAUGGGAGAGUAGCUGUAAAUACAGAUGAAGCUUUACUUGCUCCUCGCCUGCCUGCCCACCACUCACCUCCUGCUGUGUGGCCUGGUUCCUGGUUGGGGAGCCCUGACUCAAGCUUUACCCAAUUUCUUUUGGUUUAUUUUGCUUUUGUUCCCACUCAUUCCUUAAGAUGAAUAUACUGUUGAGCUAAUCAAUGGCUAACUUGCCCUAAGGCUUGAGGUUGGGGUUGAAUAAACGAGAGGCCUUUAUUCAGAUCAGCAGGAGGGGUUUCCUCCAGUAGGAUUGUUUUGUUCUGGCAUCUUUUAACUUUAAAGCUUCCCUUAAGCUGGUUUCUCUUCAUGAUUCUCCUUCCAGGUGACCAUCUCUUUCCCUUGGCUCUUUGGGCCCAGCAGUGGUGAAUUUCCAUUUUUGUUGGUUCUAGGUUACUGGACUACUCUUUGUGGUUUCCUGCUUCUCACAGUUGACCUAAAAGGAAGAAGCUGAGGCAAAAUAAGCAGAAAGUUUGUUUGGGCCAACUUGAGCAUUGCAACCUGGGAGCAGAGGUUCAAGUUGCCCUGAAUAUACACUCCAAUUAGCAGCAGUUAUAAGUAGAUUUUUUUUUUUUUCCGAGACUAUGUCUCUACAGAAAAUUAAAAAAUUAGCUGGGCAUGGUGGCUCGCACCUGUAUUCCCAGCUACUCCAGAGGCUGAGGCAGGAGGGUUGUUUGAGCCUGGGAGGUCAAGGCUGCAGUGAGCUGUGAUCACACCACUUCAUUCCAGUCUGGGUAACAGAGUGAGACCUGUCUCAAAAAAAAAAAAUUUUCAGGAAAUUAAAGUGUUAAUUGCUGCCAUCUAAUCCUUAGACUUCAUUCAGGAUUCACUGAUUGUCCUAGUAAGAUCCUUACAGCAAAAAGAUUAAGUUCAGCAUCACUUGUUGCAUUUAGUUAUCUUAACUCUAGUCUAAUUCAGUCUGGAAUAGGUCCUCAGUUUUUCCCUGAUGUUCAUGAUCUUAACACUUACGAAGAUUACAGGCCAAUUAUUUUGUAGAAUGUCCCUUUUAUUUUAUUUUAUUUUAUUUUAUUUUAUUUUAUUUUAUUUUGGAGACAGAGUUUCCCUGUGUCGCCCAGGCUGGAGUGCAGUGGCACAAUCUUGGCUCACUGCAACCUCCACCUCCAAGGUUCCAGCAGUUCUCCUGCCUCAGCUUCCUGUGUAGCUGGGAUUAUAGGUGCCUGCCACCAUGCCUGGUUAAUUUUGUAUUUUUAGUAGAGAUGGGGUUUCACCAUGUUGGCCAGUCUGGUCUCGAACUCCUGACCUCAAGUGAUCCACCCGCCUCAGCCUCCCAAAGUGCUGGGAUUAUAGGGGUGAGCCACCACCUGGUAUACAUGUCCCUUAAUUUGGAUUGUCCAGUGUCUCCUCAUGAUUACAUUCAGAUUAUGUAUCCUUGAUACCAGUAUCACUGAAUUUACUUUGAUUGCUUGAUUAAGGUGGUGUCUGCCAGAUUUUUUUCACUGUAAAGUUACUCUUUCUCUUCUUUGUAAUUAAUAAAUAUUUUGUAUUUAAUAAAUAUUUUGUAGGAAGUACUUUGAAACUAUGUAUUCCGGCCCUCAUCAGACUUUCAAAUUAUUUAUAUCUGUGAUCCAUGGUUAUAUUAUAUAUUAUAUCUUUGAUUCAUGGUUUCUCAUUUUAUACAGUGGAUUACAACCUGUUACUAUCAUUGCUUAUUGUGUUAAAAGAAAAAUUUUAGACAAAUUUAACAGAGCUUAAUUGAGCAAAGAAGAAUUUACAAAUAAGGCAGCCCCUAGAACUACGAUAGGUUCAGAUACAGCCUGAGGCUGCCACAUGGUUGGAUAACACUUUUGGACAGAAAAAGGAAAGUGACAUACAGAAAACAGAGGGAUGAGGUACAGAAACAGCUGGAUUGGUUACAGCUCAUUUUCUUCAUUUGAACACAGUUUGAACAGUUGGCUGUCUGUGAUUGGUUGAAACUUGGCUACUUGUUACAAAAGUAGGUUACAGUCUGUUUAUACAUUUAGUUAGGUUAUAAUCACUAUGUAUGGAGAAACCCUUAGGACAAACUUAAAAUCUGCAAGGAGACAGCUUUAGGCUAAACUUAACAAUUGUGAUGCUCAUUUUGUUCCUGUUAGUGGAAAAUGAUAUUUAGAAACCAAGUUCUGGGUGCUAGAUGUGAUCAUUUCUGUUGGGGUAUCACUGUUUUCAGGUCCUCUUGGUAAAGUUAGACAAAGCUAGGGAAUAUAUAUUUGCAUAUACAUUUUCAUAUAUAUACACAUACAUUUAUCUAUUUCUUUUUCAAUCUAUAUUGAAGCCUAUGAAUUCUCACUGAUUCUGAUCUAAUACCAUACAAUUCAUUCUUUUUUGUUUCCUUGACUCUACAUUAAAGGAAAAUAAUUCAUUCUUGCUUUCUUCCUCUCCUAAUUUAUAACUCCUUUAUCUGAUGAUGAGGCUGGCUGUGGUGGUGUGCAACUGUAGUCCUAGCUACUUGGAGGCCACGGCAACUCCUUGAGCCCAGGAAUUCAAAGCUGUAGUGGGCUGUGAUUGUACCACUGCACUCCAGCCUGGGAGACAGAGUGAGACCCUUAAAAACAAAAAACAAAGAAAAAGAAUAAUGAAAAAUGAAAGCCAAGUUUCUCAUUAUCACCUGUAGCUCGCUCUCUCUCUCCCUCUCUCUCUCUCUCUCUGUCUCUCUCUUUUUUUAGAGACAGGGUCUCACUUUGUUGCUUACCCUGGAGCGCAGCUGCAUGAUCAUAGCUGAUUGCAACCUUGAACUCCUGGGCUCAAGUGAUCCUCCCACCUCCGACUCUUGAUUAGCUGGGACUUCAGGCAUGAGCCACUGCCCAGCGGAUGUCUCUCCGUUUUGGAUCCAUACUUCCUUGUUCAAAUAAAACUAACUUGAAGGAAGGGGUGGGGCAGAGAGAUUUGUUUGACUGUCUCUGUGGUUACUUGCCUGGGUAUCUGUUGUUCCUGAGGUGGGAGAUCUUUAGUUGUAACUAUGAACUUUCCAAGGUUGACAGUGAGGUAUUAAGAGAUGACAAAUGGAAGUACAAAGAUUUUUCAGAGGGAGUCAUGUGACAUGGUUGUUCUCCUGUUUUGUCCAGAGCUCUGAUGUUCUGAAGGAUUGAAAUGAAAAGGAUACAUUUUAUAUUUUAUGGUGAUACAGUCCUGGGGUCAACCUCACUGAAGAGAGGCCUUUAUCUGGGGACAUUAUGUGGGGCUUCAAGGUUUUCCAGGAUUUAGGGAUGGAAGUACUGUCUGGAGUUGCCAAAGGCUAUAACAUAUGCCUUUUUGCUUAUGGACAGACAGGCUCUGGGAAGACAUAUACCAUGCUGGGGACCCCAGCCUCUGUUGGGUUGACACCACGGAUAUGUGAGGGUCUCUUCGUCAGGGAGAAAGACUGUGCCUCACUGCCUUCCUCCUGUAGGAUAAAAGUAAGUUUUCUAGAAAUCUAUAAUGAACGGGUGCGGGAUCUGUUGAAGCAAUCUGGUCAAAAAAAGUCCUAUACCCUGCGGGUCAGGGAGCAUCCAGAGAUGGGGCCCUAUGUACAAGGUUUAUCUCAACAUGUAGUUACCAAUUAUAAGCAAGUAAUCCAACUCUUGGAGGAGGGAAUUGCAAACAGAAUCACAGCAGCCACCCAUGUUCAUGAGGCCAGCAGCAGAUCCCACGCCAUUUUCACGAUCCACUACACGCAGGCAAUCCUGGAGAACAACCUCCCUUCUGAAAUGGCUAGCAAGAUCAACCUUGUGGACCUAGCAGGCAGCGAAAGAGCAGAUCCCAGUUACUGUAAGGACCGCAUUGCUGAAGGAGCCAAUAUCAACAAGUCCCUUGUGACUCUAGGAAUUGUCAUCUCCACCUUAGCCCAGAACUCCCAAGUUUUCAGCAGCUGCCAGAGCCUCAACAGCUCAGUCAGCAAUGGUGGUGACAGUGGGAUCCUUAGCUCUCCUUCUGGGACCAGCAGUGGAGGGGCACCCUCCCGAAGGCAGUCUUAUAUCCCAUACCGAGACUCUGUGUUGACCUGGCUGCUGAAGGACAGCCUUGGAGGCAACUCUAAAACCAUCAUGGUUGCCACGGUGUCUCCUGCACACACUAGCUACAGUGAGACCAUGAGCACACUGAGAUAUGCAUCCAGUGCCAAAAACAUUAUCAACAAGCCACGAGUAAAUGAGGAUGCAAACUUAAAACUGAUUAGAGAACUCAGAGAAGAGAUUGAAAGACUGAAAGCCCUGCUGCUGAGCUUUGAACUGAGAAACUUCAGUUCAUUGAGUGAUGAAAACCUGAAGGAGCUGGUUCUCCAAAAUGAAUUGAAGAUAGACCAGCUGACUAAAGACUGGACCCAGAAGUGGAAUGAUUGGCAGGCCCUCAUGGAGCAUUACAGUGUGGACAUCAACAGGAGGAGGGCUGGGGUGGUCAUCGACUCCAGCCUGCCACACUUGAUGGCCUUGGAGGAUGAUGUGCUCAGCACAGGUGUUGUGCUCUAUCAUCUCAAGGAAGGGACAACAAAAAUAGGAAGGAUUGACUCAGACCAGGAACAGGACAUUGUCCUGCAGGGUCAGUGGAUUGAGAGAGACCACUGCACUAUCACCAGUGCCUGUGGUGUAGUUGUUCUACGACCUGCCCGUGGGGCCCGCUGUACAGUCAAUGGCCGGGAGGUCACUGCCUCCUGCCGUCUGACUCAAGGAGCUGUCAUAACCCUGGGGAAGGCACAGAAGUUCCGAUUCAACCACCCAGCAGAGGCUGCUGUCCUGCGGCAGCGAAGGCAGGUUGGAGAGGCUGCUGCUGGUCGUGGCUCGUUGGAGUGGCUGGAUUUGGAUGGAGAUCUCGCUGCCUCCCGGCUGGGUCUCUCCCCUUUGCUUUGGAAGGAAAGGAGAGCGCUUGAAGAGCAAUGUGACGAGGACCAUCAGACACCGAGGGAUGGAGAGACAUCCCACAGGGCCCAGAUUCAGCAGCAGCAGAGCUACGUAGAGGAUUUGAGGCAUCAAAUCCUAGCAGAAGAGAUUCGAGCUGCGAAGGAACUGGAAUUUGACCAAGCUUGGAUUAGCCAGCAGAUUAAAGAAAACCAGCAGUGUCUGCUCAGAGAAGAGACCUGGCUGGCCAGCUUGCAACAGCAGCAGCAAGAAGACCAGGUAGCAGAGAAAGAACUUGAGGCAUCUGUGGCACUUGAUGCUUGGCUUCAGACAGAUCCUGAGAUUCAGCCAUCCCCAUUUGUCCAAAGUCAGAAAAGGGUGGUGCACCUGCAGCUCCUGCGGAGACACACUCUUCGGGCAGCAGAGCGGAAUGUCCGGCGGAAAAAGGUCUCAUUCCAGCUAGAGAGAAUCAUCAAAAAGCAGAGGCUGCUGGAGGCCCAGAAGAGACUGGAGAAGCUCACGACAUUGUGCUGGCUCCAGGAUGACAGCACCCAGGAGCCCCCAUACCAGGUCCUCAGCCCUGAUGCCACAGUCCCACGGCCUCCAUGUAGAAGCAAAUUGACGAGUUGCAGUUCUUUGAGCCCCCAAAGACUCUGCAGCAAGCACAUGCCCCAGCUACACAGCAUUUUCCUAAGUUGGGAUCCCUCUACCACAUUGCCACCUAGGCCUGACCCUACACACCAAACAUCAGAGAAAACAUCAUCAGAAGAGCAUUUGCCACAGGCUGCUUCCUACCCUGCAAGGACAGGGUGCCUCCGCAAGAACGGCCUGCAUUCCUCAGGUCAUGGGCAGCCCUGCACAGCCAGAGCAGCCUUGGCCAGGAAGGGAGCCUCAGCUCCAGACGCUUGCCUCACCAUGAGUCCCAACUCUGUUGGCAUCCAGGAAAUGGAGAUGGGGGUUAAGCAGCCCCAUCAGAUGGUGAGCCAGGGCUUAGCAUCUCUGAGGAAAUCAGCUAACAAACUAAAGCCAAGGCAUGAGCCAAAGAUCUUCACCUCUACUACCCAGACCAGAGGGGCGAAGGGACUAGCAGACCCUAGCCACACACAAGCUGGGUGGCGAAAAGAAGGGAACCUUGGGACCCACAAGGCUGCUAAGGGAGCCAGUUGCAAUUCCUUGUAUCCUCAUGGACCCAGGCAGACUGCUGGGCACGGAAAGGCAGUCAAGACUUUUUGGACAGAAUACAAACCACCUUCUCCAAGCAGGGCAUCAAAAAGGCAUCAGAGGGUUCUGGCAACUAGGGUCAGAAAUAUUACCAAAAAGUCCUCUCACUUGCCUCUUGGCAGUCCUUUGAAGAGACAACAAAAUACAAGGGACCCAGACACCAUGGUCCCACUCACAGAUUUCAGCCCAGUAAUGGAUCAUUCAAGAGAAAAAGACAAUGAUUUAUCUGACACAGAUAGCAACUACUCAUUGGAUUCUCUCUCAUGUGUCUAUGCCAAAGCCCUGAUAGAGCCACUGAAGCCAGAGGAGAGGAAAUGGGAUUUCCCAGAGCCAGAGAACUCUGAAAGUGAUGACAGCCAACUAUCUGAGGACUCACUGGCUGAGAAGAGGUACCAAAGCCCCAAAAACAGGCUAGGGGGCAAUCGUCCCACCAACAACCGUGGCCAACCCAGGACCAGAACUAGAGCUUCUGUGAGGGGCUUCACUGCAGCCUCAGACAGUGACCUACUUGCUCAAACUCAUAGGAGCUUCUCCUUGGAUAGCCUGAUUGAUGCAGAGGAAGAACUGGGGGAAGAUCAGCAAGAAGAACCUUUCCCUGGUUCAGCUGACGAGAUACCCACAGAGACUUUUUGGCACCUGGAGGACUCUAGUCUGCCUGUAAUGGACCAAGAGGCAAUAUGCAGGCUUGGUCCCAUCAACUACAGAACAGCAGCUAGGCUGGAUGCCGUCCUGCCAAUGAGCAGUUCGUUUUACCUUGAUCCUCAGUUCCAACCCCAUUGUGAGCUCCAACCCCAUUGUGAGCUCCAACCCCAUUGUGAGCUCCAGCCCCAUUGUGAGCAGGCUGAAUCACAGGUAGAGCCAAGCUACUCUGAACAAGCCGACUCUCUCCAAGGCAUGCAGCUUUCAAGAGAGAGCCCACUGAUGUCCAUGGAUUCCUGGUUUUCCUGUGACUCUAAGAUCAACCCCAGCAGCCCCCCAGGAAUAGUGGGUUCUUUAUGUCCAAGUCCUGAUAUGCAGGAAUUUCACUCCUGUAAGGGGGAGAGGCCUGGAUACUGGCCAAAUACUGAGGAACUAAAGCCAUCAGAUGCAGAAACGGUUCUGCCAUAUAGCUCCAAACUGCACCAAGGCAGUACUGAGCUCCUCUGCAGUGCAAGAGAUGAGCACACAGCCUCUGCUGCUGAUACGUCUAGGCUGUCUCUCUGGGGAAUUCAAAGGCUUAUUCAACCAGGAGCUGAUGGCACCUUUCAGGGCAGAUGUAUCCCUGACAUGACCCAGCAGGGCAGCUCUGAAGCAUCCCACAAUUCUAGCGUAUCAAACGUGCUGGCUGCCUCUGCCACCACCUUGACUCAUGUAGGCAGCACCCAUGAAAGGGAUUGGUCUGCCCUUCAGCAGAAGUACCUCCUUGAACUCUCUUGUCCUGUUUUGGAGGCCAUAGGAGCACCCAAGCCAGCUUACCCCUACCUUGAGGAAGACUCUGGUUCCCUGGCCCAAGCUUCUAGCAAAGGAGGAGAUACUCUAUUGCCAGUUGGCCCUAGGGUAUCUAGCAAUCUGAAUCUCAACAACUUUCCAGUCCAUCUGUCCAGAAUCAGGCGUUUGAGGGCAGAGAAAGAACAGGACAGUUUAAAUGCCAAAUUAGAAGGUGUUUCAGAUUUCUUUAGCACUAGUGAGAAAGAGGCGAGUUAUGACGAAACUUAUUCGGCAGACUUAGAAUCAUUGUCUGCUUCUCGAUCUACAAAUGCACAGGUCUUUGCAACAGAGAACGCGAUACCAGAUUCCAUGACAGAAGCAUGUGAAGUCAAGCAGAACAACUUGGAAGAAUGCCUUCAGAGUUGCAGGAAACCUGGACUGAUGACUUCCUCUGAUGAGGAUUUUUUCCAGAAGAACGCUUGUCACAGUAAUGUCACUACAGCCACCAAAGCAGACCAUUGGUCCCAAGGCUGGGCUCCUCUCAGGAAAAAUAGUGCAGUCCAGCCAGGGCAAUUAAGUCCCGACAGCCACUACCCACUAGAGGAAGAGAAGACAGAUUGCCAGGAGAGCUCUAAGGAAGCAGUUAGAAGACACAUAAAUGUUUCCUUUGCCCUUCCUUCAGGUCCAGAGCUAUACCUUCACUCUGCUCCCUGGAAUCCAUUGUCAUCUUCCCUGCAGCCCCCACUCUUGGAAACAUUCUAUGUGACCAAAAGCAGGGAUGCCCUGACAGAAACUGCCUUAGAGAUUCCAGCUUGCAGAGAAGUAAGGGUACCCUCCCCACCCCCCAGGGAAGCCUGGGGCUUUGGUCACAACCACCAAGCUCUCCAAGGUGCUUAUUUGAAGAAUAAUUUGCCAGUGCUGUUACAAAACCAGAAUUCUAAGAUUGCCUCAUCUCAGCAGGUCACAGCUGAGAUACCAGUUGAUCUGAAUACCAGGGAAGUCAUCAGAGAAUCAGGUAAAUGCCCUGGAAAUAUUACAGAAGAAAGCCAUGAUUCAGUUUAUUCUUCUGUUACUCAGAACAGACAUUUUCUCCCCUCUACCAGCACAAAAGUAUGUGAAUUUGAAAACCAAGUUGUAAUUUUAAAUAAAAAACACAGUUUUCCAGCACUUGAGGGAGGAGAGGUCACUGCUCAGUCCUGUUGCGGUGCUUCCUCAGACAGCACUGAGUCUGGGAAGUCUCUCCUCUUUCGUGAAUCUGAGGCACGAGAGGAAGAAGAGCUGGAUCAGAAUACGGUUCUGAGGCAGACCAUCAAUGUAAGCCUUGAGAAAGACAUGCCAGGGGAAAGUGCUGUUUCUUUGAAAUCCAGAUCAGUAGAUCGUAGAGUAAGCAGCCCAGUGAUGGUGGCCCAGGGUGGUGGCCCAACCCCUAAGUGGGAAGGGAAAAAUGAAACUGGGCUUCUUGAAAAAGGUCUUCGUCCCAAAGAUAGCUCAGAAGAGUUUAAGCUUCCAGGUACAAAGCCUGCAUAUGAAAGGUUCCAGUUAGUUGCAUGCCCUCAGGAAAGAAACCCCAGUGAAUGCAAGUCACAAGAAAUGUUAAAUCCCAACAGAGAACCUUCUGGAAAGAAACAGAAUAAAAGAGUUAAUAAUACUGAUGAAAUGGCUAGGCUAAUUAGGAGUGUAAUGCAGCUGGAAAAUGGCAUCUUAGAAAUUGAAUCUAAGCAGAAUAAGCAGGUUCAUGCUUCCCACACACCAGGAACCGAUAAGGAGUUGGUGUUCCAGGACCAGAAGGAGCAGGAGAAGACUGACCAUGCCUUUAGGCCAGACAGCUCUGGAAACCCUUUGCCCUCUAAGGAUCAGCCAUCUUCUCCAAGACAGACAGAUGAUACUGUCUUUAGGGAUAGUGAAGCUGGAGCGAUGGAGGUUAACAGCAUUGGGAACCAUCCCCAGGUCCAGAAAAUCACCCCAAACCCCUUCAGGUCAAGGGAAGGUGUACGAGAGAGUGAACCUGUGAGAGAGCACACCCACCCAGCUGGAUCGGACAGACCUGCCAGGGAUAUUUGUGAUUCUUUAGGGAAACACACAACUUGCAGAGAGUUCACCAACACUUCUCUUCACCCACAGAGAAUGAAAGCAUUGGCUAGAGCUCUGCCAUUGCAACCCAGGCUAGAGAGGUCUUCUAAGAAUAAUGGCCAGUUUGUAAAAGCAUCAGCAAGUCUCAAAGGGCAGCCUUGGGGCUUAGGAAGUCUUGAGGAAUUGGAGACUGUGAAAGGUUUUCAGGAAAGCCAAGUAGCUGAACACGUAAGUAGUUCCAACCAAGAAGAGCCAAAAGCUCAAGGUAAAGUUGAAGAAAUGCCUAUGCAAAGGGGAGGCAGCCUUCAGGAAGAAAAUAAAGUGACUCAGAAAUUUCCUAGUCUCAGCCAGCUUUGUAGGGACACGUUUUUCAGGCAGGAAACUGUCAGCCCAUUACUAAGCCGGACAGAAUUCUGUACAGCUCCUCUUCACCAAGACCUGAGUAAUACCUUGCCCUUGAAUUCUCCAAGGUGGCCAAGAAGGUGUCUUCAUGUACCUGUUGCUCUAGGCAUCUCUUCACUUGACUGUGUGCUGGAUCUCACAAUGUUGAAAAUUCAUAACAGUCCCUUGGUAACUGGAGUAGAGCAUCAGGACCAGAGUACGGAGACCAGAAGCCACAGCCCCGAAGGAAAUGUUAGAGGGCGUUCCUCUGAGGCACACACUGCCUGGUGUGGGUCUGUGCGAUCCAUGGCCAUGGGAUCUCAUAGUCAAUCUGGUGUACCAGAGAGCAUUCCUCUGGGGACAGAGGACAGGAUCUCAGCAAGCACCAGCCCCCAAGACCAUGGAAAGGACCUCAGAAUCACCUUGCUGGGUUUCAGUACCAGUGAAGAUUUUGCUUCUGAAGCCGAGGUGGCUGUACAAAAAGAAAUAAGAGUCAGUUCACUGAACAAGGUCUCUAGCCAGCCUGAAAAGAGGGUCAGCUUCUCCUUGGAAGAGGAUAGUGACCAAGCCAGCAAGCCAAGGCAGAAGGCAGAGAAGGAGACUGAGGACGUCGGACUGACCAGCGGUGUUUCCUUAGCACCUGUUUCCCUGCCGAGGGUGCCCAGUCCAGAGCCUAGGCUGUUGGAGCCCUCUGACCAUGCAUCCAUGUGCCUGGCCAUCUUGGAGGAGAUCAGACAGGCAAAGGCCCAGAGAAAGCAGCUUCAUGACUUUGUGGCCAGGGGCACAGUCCUUUCUUACUGUGAAACUUUACUAGAACCCGAAUGUUCUUCAAGGGUUGCUGGCAGGCCUCAGUGUAAACAAAUAGACCAGUCAUCAUCAGACCAGACCAGGAAUGAGGGUGAAGCACCGGGAUUUCAUGUGGCAUCUCUAUCUGCUGAAGCAGGGCAGAUAGAUCUGUUACCUGAUGAGAGGAAAGUCCAGGCCACAUCUCUGUCUGCAGACAGCUUUGAAUCUCUGCCCAAUACGGAAACUGACAGAGAGCCAUGGGAUCCUGUGCAGGCUUUCUCCCAUGCUGCUCCUGCUCAAGACAGGAAACGUCGUACUGGAGAACUGAGGCAGUUCGCGGGAGCAAGUGAACCAUUUAUAUGUCACUCUAGUUCUUCUGAAAUCAUAGAGAAAAAGAAAGAUGCAACCAGAACACCUUCCUCAGCUGAUCCUUUGGCCCCAGACAGUCCUCGUUCUUCAGCACCUGUGGAGGAGGUCAGGAGGGUAGUAUCAAAGAAGGUAGUGGCUGCCUUACCUUCUCAGGCCCCUUAUGAUGAUCCUAGAGUGACUCUGCAUGAGCUAAGUCAGUCAGUUCCGCAGGAGACUGCAGAGGGCAUACCCCCUGGCAGUCAGGACAGCAGCCCAGAGCAUCAGGAACCCAGAACUCUAGACACCACAUAUGGAGAAGUUUCAGAUAAUUUGUUAGUGACUGCACAGGGAGAAAAAACAGCCCAUUUUGAAAGUCAGUCUGUGACCUGUGAUGUUCAGAAUUCUACAAGUGCCUCAGGGCCUAAGCAAGACCAUGUCCAAUGCCCUGAGGCUUCUACUGGCUUUGAAGAAGGUAGGGCAAGUCCCAAACAAGAUACCAUUCUGCCUGGAGCUCUGACAAGGGUUGCACUGGAAGCUCCCACACAGCAGUGUGUGCAGUGUAAGGAGAGUGUUGGGUCUGGGUUGACAGAAGUCUGCAGGGCUGGCAGCAAACAUUCCAGGCCAAUUCCACUGCCAGAUCAAAGACCAAGCGCAAAUCCUGGGGGAAUUGGGGAGGAAGCCCCAUGUAGACACCCAAGGGAAGCUUUAGAUGGCCCUGUCUUCUCAAGGAACCCUGAAGGCAGCAGGACUCUCAGCCCGUCUAGAGGGAAAGAGAGCAGAACUCUUCCUUGCCGACAGCCAUGCAGUUCUCAACCUGUUGCUACUCAUGCUUAUUCCUCCCAUUCCUCUACUUUACUGUGUUUUAGAGAUGGUGACCUAGGGAAGGAGCCUUUCAAGGCUGCCCCACAUACUAUCCACCCACCCUGUGUAGUACCUUCCAGGGCCUAUGAAAUGGAUGAGACAGGAGAGAUCUCUAGGGGACCUGAUGUGCACUUGACACAUGGCCUUGAGCCCAAAGAUGUUAACAGGGAAUUUAGGCUAACAGAGAGCAGCACUUGUGAGCCUUCUACUGUGGCUGCUGUCCUAUCUCGAGCUCAAGGCUGCAGAUCCCCUUCUGCUCCUGACGUGAGGACAGGUUCCUUCAGCCACUCAGCUACUGAUGGAAGCGUGGGGUUAAUAGGGGUUCCUGAGAAAAAGGUUGCUGAGAAGCAAGCAAGCACAGAACUUGAGGCUGCCUCUUUCCCUGCAGGCAUGUACUCUGAGCCCCUGAGGCAGUUUAGGGACAGCUCUGUAGGUGACCAGAAUGCACAGGUGUGUCAAACCAAUCCAGAACCACCUGCAACAACUCAGGGACCACACACCCUGGAUUUAAGUGAAGGGUCUGCUGAGAGCAAGUUGGUGGUAGAGCCACAGCAUGAAUGUUUAGAAAAUACCACUAGAUGUUUUUUGGAAAAGCCACAAUUUUCCACUGAGUUGAGGGAUCACAAUCGCUUGGAUUCCCAAGCCAAGUUUGUAGCAAGGUUAAAACAUACCUGCAGCCCCCAGGAAGACAGUCCCUGGCAGGAAGAAGAGCAGCACAGAGACCAGGCUUCAGGUGGUGGAGAAGGCUUCGCCCAGGGUGUGAAUCCCCUUCCUGAUGAAGAUGGCUUAGAUGGCUGUCAGAUUUUAGAUGCUGGGAGAGAGGAGGUGGCUGUGGCCAAGCCUCCUGUGUCCAAGAUUUUAUCACAGGGCUUCAAAGACCCAGCCACUGUGUCCUUGAGGCAAAAUGAAACACCGCAGCCUGCUGCUCAGAGGAGUGGCCACCUCUACACUGGCAGAGAGCAGCCAGCACCCAACCACAGGGGCUCACUUCCUGUGACUACAAUCUUCUCUGGCCCCAAACACUCCAGGUCCUCCCCCACACCACAGUUCUCAGUUGUCGGCUCUUCUCGUUCUCUUCAGGAGCUGAACUUGAGUGUGGAGCCUCCUUCCCCUACAGACGAAGAUACACAGGGGCCUAACAGAUUGUGGAACCCACAUCUCAGGGGCUAUUCCUCAGGAAAGUCAGUGGCAAGAACAUCUCUGCAGGCUGAGGACAGCAAUCAGAAAGCCUCAUCUCGCUUGGAUGAUGGGACUACCGAUCACAGGCACCUGAAGCCUGCCACCCCUCCUUAUCCAAUGCCUUCCACUCUCUCACACAUGCCAACCCCUGAUUUCACGACCAGCUGGAUGUCUGGUACUUUGGAACAAGCCCAACAGGGAAAGCGAGAGAAACUGGGUGUCCAGGUUAGGCCAGAAAAUUGGUGCUCUCAGAUGGACAAAGGAAUGCUGCACUUUGGCUCCAGUGACAUCAGUCCCUAUGCGCUGCCGUGGCGUCCGGAGGAGCCUGCACGUAUCAGCUGGAAGCAGUAUAUGUCUGGCAGUGCAGUCGAUGUUUCCUGCAGCCAGAAGCCCCAGGGGCUGACACUAUCAAAUGUGGCCCGGUGCUCCAGCAUGGACAAUGGCCUAGAAGACCAGAACUCCCCUUUCCACUCCCACCUCAGCACUUACGCCAAUAUUUGUGAUCUGUCAACCACACACAGCAGCACUGAGAAUGCCCAGGGUUCAAAUGAGGCCUGGGAAGUAUUCCGAGGGAGUUCUUCAAUUGCCUUAGGAGACCCCCACAUCCCGACGAGCCCUGAAGGAGUAGCCCCCACUUCGGGUCAUGACAGAAGGCCUCAGUUCAGGGGCCCUUCUGGUGAAGCAGACUGUCUGAGGAGUAAGCCCCCCUUGGCCAAAGGAAGUGCUGCAGGUCCAGUGGAUGAGAUUAUGCUGCUGUAUCCAUCAGAGGCAGGCUGCCCUGUGGGACAGACCAGGACGAACACAUUCGAACAGGGCACACAGACCCUCGGCAGCAGGCGCCACUGGAGCAGCACUGACAUCUCCUUUGCUCAGCCUGAAGCCAGUGCAGUAUCAGCCUUUGAUCUGGCCUCAUGGACCAGCAUGCACAAUCUGUCUCUCCACCUCUCACAGCUCCUGCACAGUACCUCAGAGCUGCUUGGGAGUCUCUCCCAGCCAGAUGUGGCCAGAAGGGAGCAGAACACCAAGAGGGACAUCCCAGAUAAAGCCCCACAGGCCCUGAUGAUGGAUGGCUCUACUCAGACCACUGUGGAUGAGGGCAGCCAGACUGACCUCACCUUACCCACCCUGUGCCUCCAGACUUCAGAGGCUGAACCUCAGGGAGCCAAUGUGAUCCUUGAAGGGCUAGGCUCAGAUACCUCGACUGUGUCUCAAGAAGAGGGAGAUGUGCCAGGGGUACCUCAGAAGAGAGAGGCAGAGGAAACAGCACAGAAAAUGGCUCAGCUCCUCUAUCUUCAGGAAGAAAGCACUCCCUACAAGCCCCAGAGCCCUUCAAUACCCUCAUCCCACUUGAGGUUUCAGAAAGCCCCCGUUGGGCAGCAUCUUCCUUCUGUGAGCCCCUCAGUUUCUGAUGCUUUCCUGCCUCCCAGCUCCCAGCCAGAGGAGUCAUAUUGCUUAGUUGUCAGCAGUCCCAGUCCCAGCUCCCCUCAUUCCCCAGGGCUCUUUCCCAGUACUUCCGAGUAUCCUGGGGACUCCAGGGUCCAGAAGAAGCUGGGCCCCACAAGUGCUUUGUUCGUGGACAGGGCCUCCUCCCCAAUCCUCACUCUUAGUGCCAGCACCCAAGAGCCGGGUCUUUCCCCAGGCUCUUUGACCCUCUCAGCCCCUUCAACUCACCCUGUUGAAGGCCACCAGAAGCUUGACUCCAGCCCAGACCCUGUUGAUGCCCCAAGGACUCCAAUGGAUAAUUAUUCCCAAACCACUGACGAGUUAGGUGGCUCCCAGAGAGGUAGAAGUUCCUUACAAAGGAGUAAUGGGAGAUCCUUCCUUGAGUUGCACUCCCCACACAGCCCACAGCAGAGUCCAAAACUCCAAUUUAGUUUCUUAGGGCAGCACCCUCAGCAGCUUCAGCCCAGGACAACUAUCGGGGUCCAAAGCAGACUGCUGCCACCACCACUGAGGCACAGGAGCCAAAGGCUGGGCAACAGCUUUGUGCCUGAGAAGGUGGCUUCCCCGGAGCAUUGCCCACUGAGCGGUAGGGAGCCAAGUCAGUGGCAGAGCAGGACAGAAAAUGGAGGUGAGAGUUCAGCAUCUCCAGGGGAACCACAACGCACUCUGGACCGACCUUCUUCAUGGGGAGGCCUCCAGCACCUCAGCCCCUGCCCUGUCUCUGAGUUGACUGAUACUGCAGGGCUCCGAGGUUCUGCCUUGGGCCUCCCUCAGGCCUGCCAACCUGAGGAGUUACUGUGCUUCAGUUGCCAGAUGUGCAUGGCCCCUGAGCACCAGCACCACAGUCUGAGGGACCUCCCGGUGCAUAACAAAUUUAGUAACUGGUGUGGGGUUCAGAAGGGCUCACCUGGGGGGUUGGACAUGACUGAGGAGGAGCUGGGGGCCAGCGGUGAUCUCAGCUCUGAAAAGCAGGAACAGAGUCCCCCACAACCUCCUAAUGACCACAGCCAGGAUUCUGAGUGGUCCAAGAGGGAGCAGAUCCCCCUGCAAGUUGGGGCCCAGAACCUCUCACUCAGCGUGGAACUCACAGAAGCGAAACUGCACCAUGGCUUUGGGGAGGCCGAUGCCCUGCUCCAGGUGCUGCAGAGUGGGACAGGGGAGGCGCUUGCUGCUGAUGAACCUGUGACAUCCACCUGGAAGGAGCUCUAUGCACGGCAAAAAAAGGCCAUUGAGACCCUCAGGAGAGAGCGGGCUGAGCGACUUGGGAACUUCUGCCGGACGCGAAGCCUUAGCCCUCAGAAACAACUGAGCCUCCUGCCCAACAAAGAUCUCUUCAUCUGGGAUCUUGACUUGCCCAGCAGACGCCGAGAAUACCUGCAGCAACUGAGGAAGGAUGUUGUGGAGACCACCAGGAGCCCAGAGUCAGUGUCAAGGUCAGCUCACACACCCUCUGACAUAGAGUUGAUGCUGCAAGACUACCAGCAGGCCCAUGAGGAGGCCAAGGUGGAGAUUGCCCGGGCCCGAGACCAACUGCGGGAGCGGACUGAACAAGAGAAGCUGAGAAUCCACCAGAAGAUCAUUUCCCAGCUAUUGAAGGAAGAGGAUAAACUACAUACCUUGGCCAAUUCCAGCUCCCUGUGCACCAGCUCUAAUGGAAGCCUCUCGUCUGGCAUGACCUCUGGCUAUAAUAGCAGCCCAGCCUUGUCAGGCCAGCUCCAGUUCCCAGAGAAUAUGGGGCAUACAAACUUGCCUGAUUCCAGGGAUGUAUGGAUAGGGGAUGAGCGAGGAGGCCAUUCUGCAGUGAGGAAGAACUCUGCCUACAGCCACAGAGCCUCCCUGGGCAGUUGCUGCUGUUCACCAUCCAGUCUGUCCAGCUUGGGGACCUGCUUUUCCUCCUCCUACCAGGAUUUGGCCAAGCAUGUCGUGGACACUUCUAUGGCUGAUGUAAUGGCUGCUUGUUCGGAUAAUUUGCACAACCUCUUCAGCUGCCAGGCAACUGCUGGCUGGAACUAUCAGGGUGAGGAGCAGGCGGUGCAGCUUUACUACAAGGUGUUUUCUCCCACUCGGCAUGGCUUCCUGGGGGCAGGUGUGGUGUCCCAGCCGCUGUCUCGUGUGUGGGCGGCUGUCAGUGACCCCACUGUGUGGCCCCUGUAUUACAAGCCCAUCCAGACAGCAAGGCUGCAUCAGCGAGUGACCAACAGCAUCAGCCUGGUGUACUUGGUGUGCAACACCACCCUGUGCGCACUGAAGCAGCCACGGGAUUUCUGUUGUGUCUGCGUGGAAGCCAAAGAGGUGCCUGCCUUGGUGGGUCACCUGUCUGUCAUGGCAGCCCAGUCUGUGUAUGAUACAUCCAUGCCAAGACCCAGCAGAAAAAUGGUUCGCGGGGAGAUCCUGCCCAGUGCCUGGAUCUUGCAGCCCAUCACUGUGGAAGGGAAGGAAGUCACCAGAGUCAUCUACUUGGCCCAGGUGGAACUUGGUGCUCCAGGCUUCCCACCUCAGCUCCUGAGCUCUUUCAUCAAACGGCAGCCACUGGUUAUAGCCAGACUGGCUUCCUUCCUUGGUAGGUAGCAUCUCACCGUCAAGAUGGUGCUGCUGAGAUGCAGGCCCAGGCUGCUCAAGAGAGACACUGUGGCAGCUCCUUGUUACUUUCCAUACCACAGUGCAGGAAAAGCUGAUGCUACCUGCUGUGGCCGAUUGGGGCAGACAGCACUGGCCCAGGGAUGCUAGCAAAGCCCAGUCAGUACUUGGUCACAGCUGGCACCAGUGCAGAGCAAACGGCCUGAGCUCCUGGCCCAGACUAUCCAGAGUGAAUGCAGCUCCGCUCACCUUUUGGAUUUCUCACCUUUCUUUCCUGUUUCUGGGACUCUGCGGCAGACAGGACACUUAAGGACCAGGACUGGGCACAGCCAGCAGAGCCGGGGACUGCAGUGCUUUGGCAAGGUGCUUCCGCAGGCUGGUAGGGAAGCAGGCAGCCACUGGCCAAGACUCUGUUCUGAAUCUACCUCCUCUAGCAUUCAGCUCUACUGUGUGAUGGGACGUUAAAAAUACCAAAACAGAAAGAGGGUUUAAAAAACAGCUGCACAAACCAGAACACCGAUUCAGAAUCUUUUCUCCCUCUUGAGUUUUUGCAAAAUACUUUAUUAUUGAUUUUUGCUUUUUUUCUCCCUUUCCCUCCCAGGAGAAGACAUUUGGGUCUUGGCCUGAGGCAGGGGUGUUGAGCGAUGAUGCUCUGAUAUGGAGCUGUCACUCUAGAGCUCGGUCAGAUGGAAGACACUAUAGAACCAGGUUGGACAGAUUUGGGGUCAGGGUUGGAGGCUGAGUUCUUUUGAGGACUGGUUGGAGUGGCAGCCAGAUGGUGGCUGCUGACAAGGCAAGAGGAAUUUCAGAGAUUAAACAUUGUCCUUUGAGGAAGGGAGAGGAGGUGAAUGAACUCCCAGAGGAGGUGAGUGGCUUGUUGGGAGGAAGCUCAGUUCCAGAACUUACCUCAGUGCACUUGGGAGGGGUGGAGUCCUGAGCAUUCCAUGAUUUCUGCCCUGGCCCCACCUAUCCUAGGAUGGGGUGGGAUGGAGAGUGGGUUCAGUUUUCUUGUACUUUAGCCUGGCUGAACAUGAACUUUGUGUUUACCUGGAAGUGGUAGGGGUGGGAGAGAUUCUCAUCUUUAGUUCUGGUGCCCAAAAUCUUUGGUAGAUGGAGGGAACUGGGGAUUCAGAAGAUGUGGUAAAGGUCUAUUUCUGUAGUGUGGCAGAGAUGUGUUUUUCUAAAGUGUUUGCAGGGCAUUUUUCCCUCUUACCUCAGAUUAAGUUAUUUAUAUAUUGUUGAUUGAAGGUUUUUUAAAAUUGCUUUUAAACUUCUAUUUCUCGGGUAAAUUUUUUGGUGACAUGAUAUAUUUAACACCCUAUUUAUAUACUCCUACCUCUUUUCAUAUAAAUCUCUUACUAAGACUACUGACCAAAAAAGAACAUUUUAAAAUUAAAAGUCCUCUGUGUACUUUA